AGUUCACACGUGGCGCCAGCGGAGGCAGGUUGAUGUGUUUGUGCUUCCUUCUACAGCCAAUAUGAAAAGGCCUAGUAAGUGGGGUCGGGAGGCGGGCGUGGAGGGACCCACGUCUGGAAGUUGCUGCAGCCACCACGACGCUCUUCUACGGCUACGGCUUUGUCUCUGCUGAGUUAAAGAAAGCAAGUAAACGCAUGACCUGCCAUAAGCGGUAUAAAAUCCAAAAAAAGGUUCGAGAACAUCAUCGAAAAUUAAGAAAGGAGGCUAAAAAGCGGGGUCACAAGAAGCCUAGGAAAGACCCAGGAGUUCCAAACAGUGCUCCCUUUAAGGAGGCUCUUCUUAGGGAAGCUGAGCUAAGGAAACAGAGGCUUGAAGAACUAAAACAGCAGCAGAAACUUGACAGGCAGAAGGAACUAGAAAAGAAAAGAAAACUUGAAACUAAUCCUGAUAUUAAGCCAUCAAAUGUGGAACCUAUGGAAAAGGAGUUUGGGCUUUGCAAAACUGAGAACAAAGCCAAGUCGGGCAAACAGAAUUCAAAGAAGCUGUACUGCCAAGAACUUAAAAAGGUGAUUGAAGCCUCCGAUGUUGUCCUAGAGGUGUUGGAUGCCAGAGAUCCUCUUGGUUGCAGAUGUCCUCAGGUAGAAGAGGCCAUUGUCCAGAGUGGACAGAAAAAGCUGGUACUUAUAUUAAAUAAAUCAGAUCUGGUACCAAAGGAGAAUUUGGAGAGCUGGCUAAAUUAUUUGAAGAAAGAAUUGCCAACAGUGGUGUUCAGAGCCUCAACAAAACCAAAGGAUAAAGGGAAGAUAACCAAGCGUGUGAAGGCAAAGAAGAAUGCUGCUCCAUUCAGAAGUGAAGUCUGCUUUGGGAAAGAGGGCCUUUGGAAACUUCUUGGAGGUUUUCAGGAAACUUGCAGCAAAGCCAUUCGGGUUGGAGUAAUUGGUUUCCCAAAUGUGGGGAAAAGCAGCAUUAUCAAUAGCUUAAAACAAGAACAGAUGUGUAAUGUUGGUGUAUCCAUGGGGCUUACAAGGAGCAUGCAAGUUGUCCCCUUGGACAAACAGAUCACAAUCAUAGAUAGUCCGAGCUUCAUCGUAUCUCCACUUAAUUCCUCCUCUGCGCUUGCUCUGCGAAGUCCAGCAAGUAUUGAAGUAGUAAAACCGAUGGAGGCUGCCAGUGCCAUCCUUUCCCAGGCUGAUGCUCGACAGGUAGUACUGAAAUAUACUGUCCCAGGCUACAGGAAUUCUCUGGAAUUUUUUACUGUGCUUGCUCAGAGAAGAGGUAUGCACCAAAAAGGUGGAAUCCCAAAUGUUGAAGGUGCUGCCAAACUGCUGUGGUCUGAGUGGACAGGUGCCUCAUUAGCUUACUAUUGCCAUCCCCCUACAUCUUGGACUCCUCCUCCAUAUUUUAAUGAGAGUAUUGUGGUAGACAUGAAAAGCGGCUUCAAUCUGGAAGAACUGGAAAAGAACAAUGCACAGAGCAUAAGAGCCAUCAAGGGCCCUCAUUUGGCCAAUAGCAUCCUUUUCCAGUCUUCCGGUCUGACAAAUGGAAUAAUAGAAGAAAAGGACAUACAUGAAGAAUUGCCAAAACGGAAAGAAAGGAAGCAGGAGGAGAGGGAGGAUGACAAAGACAGUGACCAGGAAACUGUUGAUGAAGAAGUUGAUGAAAACAGCUCAGGCAUGUUUGCUGCAGAAGAGACAGGGGAGGCACUGUCUGAGGAGACUACAGCAGGUGAACAGUCUACAAGGUCUUUUAUCUUGGAUAAAAUCAUUGAAGAGGAUGAUGCUUAUGACUUCAGUACAGAUUAUGUGUAACAGAACAAUGGCUUUUUAUGAUUUUUUUUUUAACAUUUUAAGCAGACUGCUAAACUGUUCUCUGUAUAAGUUAUGGUAUGCAUGAGCUGUGUAAAUUUUGUGAAUAUGUAUUAUAUUAAAACCAGGCAACUUGGAAUCCCUAAAUUCUGUAAAAAGACAAUUCAUCUCAUUGUGAGUGGAAGUAGUUAUCUGGAAUAAAAAAAGAAGAUACCUAUUGAAAAA